CCAUGAAAUUUGGUUAAGCAAACACUAUGAGGACAUUCUGUAACCUGCAGAGAGAAAAGGGCUGUUUUUCAGAAUAGAGACUAUAACCUGGAUUAUAUUUGAUGUAUAAUUACUUGUUAAUGACUGAUUUAGUUCUAAGUUACAGUUUUAAGAAUUUUACAUUAAGAAAUAUUAUCUUUGUGUCUGUUUAGGUCUUUCCCAGGGGAACAUUUACUCAGAAAUUUUAAAACUAACUGAUCUCUGGGAAUCAUUAAAUUUGAAAAUAUCUGUGACAUAGUCCAAUAGAGAAAAAUUAUUAAAGUUGAUCACCCCAGGUUAUAAGUUAUUCCUUGACUGGGACUUGGGCCAAACAUGAAUGGCCAGAGUAAAACUAUAGGCUAAAUCAAUAUCUGAAGAAUAUGGGCAUGGUGGUUAAUCAGGCUGGCCCCUGCUCAAAUGCUGUGGAACCUCUGUUGUGUGGGCUUCUUGAAUACAAUACAUAGAGAUGCAAUCUUCUCUUCAUAAUUUUCAUUUAGUGACACUCCUGGACACUCAUUGGAAAAAUUUUGGACACACAAUAGAAAUGAAAAUCAAUAGUAAAUCACCCAAAUAUAGACCCUCUAAAGACUGUAUGAUGUUGCUUUGAAAAUUUUAAAUUUAAUCUAUUUAACAUUUGCAUGCAUUAACCCACUUGUCAUAUUGGGUCAAAUAAUAUGAAAUACUUCUAAGAAGUGGUGAUCAGUUCUUUAUAUUUUUCUGCAAAAUUUCAGCACAUUAAUUAAAAAGAUAGAAUUGAUUUGGUUUCAUAUCUAAAAAUUUGUUUUCAAAAUAAAAAAUUUAACUUCAUAUAACCCUUUCCUGAGUGAGGAAUUAUAUUUAGAUUGUAACAAUUUAUUUUAGAAUGAAAAUUAGGUUUGGUUUGCUCAGUCUCACUCGUAAGCAUAAUGACUUUAUUUUCUUCAUGGGGAAUUCUGAGCCUUUGGCCUUUUCCUAUUCCCACAUCUCCGGGAGUUCAGUCUAGUUUCUUUAGCAAAGGGAAAAUAAUAGUUUUCUAAUAUGAUUUCGGAUUUUGGACGUACAUUUAGGAGUUUCCAGAGCUUUCUCACAGUUCUGUACAUGAGUUUCAAAGCAGGUCCAAAGUCUCACCAUGAACUAAGGGUCAGCAUCAGAUUCAGACCAUCCUUGAUAUGGAUUUUUUUUCCCUGUAGAGCUUAUACUCUAUUCUAAAUCAAGUAUAUUUUUAGUAAUAACUCUAGAAAAAGCAGUAAAAUAUAUAAGCAGCUACUCAGAAUCUAAGAUUCAGCAGGUUUUUUGAGCUUAUCUACUACUGGCUCUUUUAUUUUUAGUGUUCUAUCAUCAAAAGUAAUAUAUAUUUUUAAAAUUGUACACUUAACGAUAUACUAAGGAUUGGGCAAGAUGCCUUACAUCAUUUUGACAACAACUACAUUUGCUUUCUCCAUUUUACAGAUUAAGAAACUAAUGUUCAAGAAAUUACAUAACUUGCCCAGUGAUAUACAACUGUUUUUUUCAACACCACUUUAUUGAGGAAGGAUUAGCAUACAAAAAGAUGUGUAUAUUUAAUAUAUAUAACUUGGUGAGUUUGGAGAUAAAUAUAUACCUGGGAAACCACCACCACAAUCUAUGCAAUAAACAUGUCUAUCUUGGUUGAGUUUCAAACCCAGUUCUGUUGAUUGUCAAAGCUCUUUCUUUAUGUUAUGCUGUCUCUAUACGAUGAAGCUAUAACUCACUAUCUUGUCCCUUUCCACUUGAGAAUCAAGAGAGUUGGUAAUAGAAGAAGUCAAGAUGUACCCAUUUCAAAACAGGCUGUCCUUUUAUUGGAUUUAGGCUAGGUGAAAAGGAAAAGGAGGCGGGGAAUAGGGAAUAAAAUGAAUAAAAUUGAGAAUUGUAAAAAGCAAAAAUUAAAUGUUUUAUUUAUCUUCAACCAUUCUUUAUGAUGUGUUUACUGUUUCUACAAGAUAUAACCCCUGCCCUCUUAGAGCUUAUUUACUUGAGGAGGAUAAGCUAGCGCAUAUUAAUUCUGAUUAUACAAAAGAGAUUUAGGAAGAAGGUGUGUGACUUCAUGGAACUUUUUGCCUUAAACAGAAUCACCAUGCAUCUAUACUUAAGCUGACAUAAUGUAAAAAGAAAAUCAUAUUAAAAUUUUUGCUUUAUUCUACAUAAUCUAAUUUAUGGCAUGCUAAGGUUUAAGAACAAAGGUUCUGAACUCCAGAUAUGAGCCUCUGUUAGAGAUUAGAGCACAAUGUGUGGUUUUAGAUGCAAGUUAAUAUCAACAAAAGGAAAGGGCUCAAAAAAUUGUACACAGAGGCUCUCCUAAACAGGUCUGCAACAAUAGAUUAAUUUAUGUGUUUACUUGUUUGCUGGCUUCCUAGUGCAUUCUAUACUGGCUAUAAGGAAUUCGAAUUUGGGAGAAUACAUGGGAUCCUUCAUAUGCAAAUCAAGUUUACACAUCAACCAUCAGAAAACACGAUAGAGCUAUUUUUAUAUUUGUGAGUAAGCUUUUUCCUUAGGAUCAAGGACUUGGAGUUCUUGUUUCAGAGCAUACUCUGCAGCUACAUUACAGAGAGAAUUAACUGGAAUCUAAUCGCAUACUUAAGUUCAGGAGCUCAGUGUGGUAACCAUCUGAUCCAGUGAGUUAUCGAAUCUUGAGUUAAAAGAACAAAAACACAAUAACAAAGUUUUAGGCUUGUCUGUCUCCUGAUAAUCCUAAUUAUUUCCCACCACAUUCUUUUGCUCUCUACACACUCACCUCCUCUGUCUGUGCUCCCUCUCCAAGAGGAAAUAGAGGAAGAACCUUGGGACAUCAGUUUCUAAACUCUCUUCUAAAUUAUGCUUUCAACAGGCACCAAUCACAAGUUUGAACUCAUGUUCCUUUGGGGCUGACUAGAAGUAUAAACCUGAAGAAGGUACUAAGCUCCCUCAUUUUUCAGUUUCUCUAUCUGUGAAAAUGGUAUAAUUGAGGACACUUCUCUCUUAAGGGUAUGGAUCACCAUGCAGAUACUGAACAGGCAUGAAUGAAUUAAUCGUGCCAGAUUCUCCAACACUUCCUCAGGAGACCCUAUUGCUCUGAUCAAGAAGUUCCAUCAGCACCGAAGAAAACAGCAGCUCUGCCUUUGUUUCCUACUUUUUAGCUUUUGACCUAUAGCUGAAAAAGUCCCAGAAAGCUGAUCUUUCCAAGUUAAUCAUCCCUGAAGAGUGGCGGACUCAUUGUGCACUAAAGCAAUCCUUUCUUCUAUGUGAGCCAAAAAAAGAAAAACGGCCUGCCAGACACCUGUAAAGAGAAGGCUAUCGUCAUAUAGGAAUUUGAGGAACUGCUAUAUGGUACAUUCCUUUUCCAAAUGGGAGAGAAUAAGCUCUCAUGAUGUCCCAGAGGGCCUUAAAAUAAACAAGAGGGGAAAUUGUAACAGCUUGUCAUCUGUGCUUGUACACUAGACUUCCAUGUAGUUACUCUAGAGAAAUCUAAAUCAAAAAUGCAGAUCAUUCUUUGAAAAAUCCCCAAAUCAUACGUAGAGACUCAGACAGAUGUGGUAAAAAGAGGAAGGUUAUUUUAUACUUCGUAUCUCCAACCCACUGGCAAUCAAUCUUUUGGAAGGAACAGCAGUUGAUUGUGAAUUUAGUUUUGAACCACCAUUAGGCAAAGAUAGUUUCUCUAGAGAGAAUCAUGCCUGCUAAUUACACGUGUACCAGGCCAGAUGGAGACAAUACAGAUUUUCGAUACUUUAUUUAUGCAGUGACAUACACUGUCAUUCUUGUGCCAGGUCUCAUAGGGAAUAUAUUAGCCCUGUGGGUAUUCUAUGGUUAUAUGAAAGAAACAAAACGAGCUGUGAUAUUUAUGAUAAACUUAGCCAUUGCUGACUUACUACAAGUUCUUUCCUUGCCACUGAGGAUCUUCUACUACUUGAAUCAUGACUGGCCAUUUGGGCCUGGUCUCUGCAUGUUCUGUUUCUACCUGAAGUAUGUCAACAUGUAUGCAAGCAUCUACUUCUUGGUCUGCAUCAGUGUGCGACGAUUUUGGUUUCUCAUGUACCCCUUUCGCUUCCAUGACUGCAAACAGAAAUAUGACCUGUACAUCAGCAUUGCUGGCUGGCUGAUCAUCUGCCUUGCCUGUGUACUCUUUCCACUCCUCAGAACCAGUGAUGAUACCUCUGGCAAUAGGACCAAAUGCUUUGUGGAUCUUCCUACCAGGAAUGUCAACCUGGCCCAGUCCGUUGUUAUGAUGACCAUUGGCGAGUUGAUUGGGUUUGUAACUCCGCUUCUGAUUGUCCUAUAUUGUACCUGGAAGACGGUUUUAUCACUGCAAGAUAAAUAUCCCAUGGCCCAAGAUCUUGGAGAGAAACAGAAAGCCUUGAAGAUGAUUCUAACCUGUGCAGGGGUAUUCCUAAUUUGCUUUGCACCUUAUCAUUUCAGUUUUCCUUUAGAUUUCCUGGUGAAGUCCAAUGAAAUUAAAAGCUGCCUAGCCAGAAGGGUGAUUCUAAUAUUUCAUUCUGUGGCAUUGUGUCUUGCUAGUCUGAAUUCAUGUCUUGACCCAGUCAUAUACUACUUUUCCACUAAUGAGUUCCGAAGACGGCUUUCAAGACAAGAUUUGCAUGACAGCAUCCAACUCCAUGCAAAAUCCUUUGUGAGUAACCAUACAGCUUCCACCAUGACACCUGAAUUAUGCUAAAACAAAAAACCAAACUGAAUGUGACCUGAAAUGCAAGUACAUCAGAACAUAUCUGCAAUACCCAAGCCACAGGGAAGAACUUGCAAAACAACACAGCUUUUCAGUUCUGCUCUAUCUUACUGCUAUGGGGAAUUCACUUCUUCAAAGCAGGACCUAUUUGGAGCAUUACGAUCCACGAUUAUUGAUGUUGACAUGUCCAUGUAGUAAUUUUUCUUCAAGUCUGUAAAUCUUAAAAUAUCAAAUUUCUGUGACAUCCUAUAAACAUAUGCACUCAACUGUAGUCAGUACUUUUACCUGUGAACCUCAGGCACAAAAAGAUUAUUAGCUUGGAGUCACCAUAAACAUUUAGUUUUGUUGCAACAGAUACUGAGUCUUUAUGUUCAGAGGAAAUGUAAGUGUCUUUUUAUAUUAGUAAUCACAGUUUACAUGCCAUUUUCAUAUGUUUGGUUAUAUUUUAGUGGGAUAGAUGAUAUAUUACCCUGUGUAAAGAAAAUGUAAACAUAAGAUCAUUUUUAUCUCUCAAGUGUGAUUACUCUUCAGAGUUUGAAGAUUAAAAUAGCUAUUUUCUUCAUUUUUGUGUCAACAUGAAACAUCAUUUGUCACACCUGUUCACAGAAUGAAAAUCUGAACUCAGGCCUCUGGCAUAUUUAAACUAAGAACAAUAUACAUAUUUACAUACGACAACCCUCUGUGACUGGAAAAGAUGCCGUGUUGCAUCUACCUAGGACAGGUAGUUUGUCAAAGUCCAUACAAGGUGACUCAAUUGGGCUCUAGGCCUAGGAGAAAGCAGAAAGGUGACAAUCACAAUUCUGCUCUCUUACACUUUUUCUAAAGAACACUUCUGGAGAUGUAUGGACCCGCCUAGUAGAGGAAGUUUUUAUCAUGUUUCUAGAGAUACAUUGAGGUAAUGUUGACAGGUUCCUGCACUUUCUGAGCCUGUGGAAGAAGUAGUGCACUAAUGAAUCAUUAAACCUGGGCCAGAGUGAAAAGAUGAAGCAAAGUUGGGUAAUCUUUUUAAAAUUCUCAUCACAUUGUAUUUCUUACUCUAAUACAAGGACACUUACUUAGCUUAGACUGCCAAGUUACUUACACAAGCCAGAGUAAGUCUCUCUGCCCCAUCAUUGCAUACAUAUUACAGUCAGUCACAUGGACCCUAGAAUCCACAUUGAUUUUUUUUGGUCUAGCUUUGCCCCAGACAUACCAUUCUAAAGCCUACAAAGCCUAGCUCUUAGCAGCUGGGGAAGGCAAUUAUUUCACCUCUUGAAAAAUGCAUAGAAGAUUAAUUUGGUCAGCCUUUGGCAACCAAUGGCCAAUGACUUGCCUACUACCUGUUUGGUACUAUUGUGUGGGAAACAGACCCAGGAUAUUAGUCGUAAUUAAACCUUAGGUUGUAAGUAUUAGAAUAUUUUGAAACAUGUUUUAGCAAAAAGCUCUAACUUUAAGAAAGUUCUACUUAAAAUCUGUGUGCUAUAUAAUGAAGAUACCUUCUACGUCUCACAGAAGGAAUGUAGAACCCAAUCAAAGGCUUUAUCAUAUUUAGAGGAAAGGGGUUGUUUUAGGCAUACAGUUAUGAUACUAAUACAUUAGGGGAAAACUGGUGACAUCAAAAUGAAUUCUAAUAUCUAGACUGAUGGAAAGUUUUCUAAAGUUUUCUUUGGACAAGUGUUGAUUUUACACAUAUGUUGUUAUUAAGAUAAUACCCUAUUAGAAAACUGACUUUGUGCUGCUAGCAAGUGUAUCUAUGUGUCUCCUAACUAAUCAUUGUAAGGUAUAUGUUUUGAUGUGUUAAAUAAGUUUUCAAUAAGUGUUAAACUGUAUUUUAAAUAGGGCAUCUAUAACUGUGUCUUGUCUCUUUGCUUUAAAGUGUCUUUUGUUUGACUAUAAUUUAGUGUUGCAAUAGGAUUGCAAGUAAUAAUUUUGUGGAAUUGUGAAAUAACUGUGGGUACUUUUAAUGUGAGAGUCUUAUCUAUAGUAUUUGUGCUUAGUAUUUUCUAGAUUAGCAUGAAUUACACUUCCUAAGGUCACUUUGGAAGAUGAUUGAUUUGAUUUAAUUAACAUAUUGAUUUCACUUUGACUAUAUUUUUCUUAAAGAGGAAGGGAAAUAUUUUCAGGAGAUGUUUGACCUUCUUAGAUGAAUGGUUGAGGGUAGGGCCCAUUUGUUAGGCAGCCCAUUUACAUCAUUCCAAAAAAGGACCAGUAUUCAGUGUUAUGCUGCUUAGCUGAGGACACCCUUUUUCCCCAGGCCUGCCCAUCUACGUUUGUAUUCAGUGCUCUGAUUUACUUUAUUCACCCCUUAUCCCAUCAAUAUGUUUUGUCUUCUGCUUGAUUCCCUUGCUCUCCCAGGCAGCAACCUGAUCAAUUCAUUCACACCAUGGUGCUAAUAGCUAAUGUUAGGUUCAUAUUAAUUUACCCAGGAAUAUCUGAAUUCCAGGCUUUAGGACUAGGCAUUAAACCAAAGUGGUGACUUUCAAUGGAGGGCUAAUACAUACUGAAGCAGACAGACUGGAGGGAAAGAAAUUUUGGAUAAAGUGGGUCCCACAGCACUGCCUUUCAUAUUGCAUACAGUAAGCAAACACCUACUUUGGUUACCAUAAUGGGAAUGCUGACUUUUAAGAAAUUAAGAAAUGUAUCCAUGAACAUGGCUAUCAGUUUCUCAGAUGUCUGCUCACCUUCUUUUCAUUUUGCCUCUCUCCUUUCCUACGUUGGGCCUGAUUUUCAGGGGAAAGUCUAAACUAGUAGCUUACUAAUUUAGGAGUACUGGUGCAGCUACGAUCCAGACAGCAGCCUGUUCUCUGAGCUUCUCCAUUCCAUGGCUUAUCCAGACUUCUCAUUUAUCACUCUCUGGGUUCUAUGAAAUUGUGGUGCAAAGAGUAAACACCCUCAACCAUAGUAAUGUAUACUUCAAGAUAAAUAAUUCCACAUUUCCUAUAUAAAGUUGUUGAAUUUUGAUUCAAAAAUGCGUAAGUAUUCCAAUAAGAAAAACUUUGUAUGUAGUGAUUUCUAUGUAAAAAUAUUGUUAUUAUUAUUAUAUUCAAAUGGUUUAUAUGUUUUCAUUGUCACUCAGUUAAGCAGCCAAUUCUGUUAGCUGGUAAUUCCACAAAGAGAAGCCAUCUGCCCCAGGAGCAACAGACCAAGCUGCCUUGGUCUGAGAGGGUGCAUCUGUGGAACUCUUGCGCAACUUACAUUUUAUGUCACCUUUUGAUUUUACUCCCAAGAUACUGUGAAAAUGUUGCACUUGGAAUUUAUUUAUGGCUAUAACUUAUAAUAUUCAUUUUAAUAAUAAAGAUUGUCUUUGUAAUUACAUAGAAA